CUUUACCUCUGCACCCCAGCUCAUGGUUAUCUUGUAAAACUGAAGGUGCUUUGCACUGCAAACAGACAUGACAGCUCAGUCUCCCCUGUAGCAAGUUCUAGGGAAGGCAGGUUGGCAGAGUCCCAUUUUUGAGCUCAGUUCUCCAAGGCCCUUUGGUCAGCUUAUUUUCCUGCAGGGUGUCACAUCCCACAGUAGUCUCCACCUGGAAGACAUUGGAUCUCAUAUGUUCAGAUCAGUGUAGCCACGCUGCUCUGUGGAGAACAGUGUGAUAAAUCCUUGGUAGCAUUACGCUUUAAACUGGUGGCCACUUGCCUACCUCCUUUUAAUUUCAUUUUGUUAACAAUUGUUUCUUGAGGACCUGUUGCAUGCUGGGUGCUUUUUUCCUGGGUGAUUUCACAUUUAGCAUCUGUUUUCAUUCUCAUGACUUCUCUGUGAGGUAGCAAGUAUUGUACCCAGUUUUCUGAUAGAGGAAAUUGUGGCCCAGAGAGAUUGUUGUACCCCAAAGUAAUGAAGAUGAAUACAGUUGCAGAACCAAGUUAGAAGCCAGAUUUUUGGAGAUCCAAGGUCCAGUGAACACAGCUGUACCCCCACAGACACUUCCGAAAGUGACCACAGCCUCUUCAGCCAGUCCUGAAGAGUAUGUUCACCUUCAUCUGUCUUAAAGCACAGGCACACCUGGCUUUGGGAAAGCAUAGUUUAUCAAGAUCUGAAUUGGCUCAUUUUAGUUUUAGAAAAGGUUUCACCUAAGGCUUCUGCUUAAGAAGAGAGCAUUCCUAGGAAGUGAGCUUAAGCCCUGUUCACCCUAUUAAUCUUAAGUGAUUUGUCAGAGCAGAGUGGCAGAGAGGUGUCCUGCAGAGGUGACAACCUGAAUUUAAAUCACAGCUCAGCCGCUUACUAGCUGUGUAAUCUUGAGCAAAUUACUUAACUCUCUGAGCCUCUUCUUCCUUCUCUAUUAAAGGGGAGUGAUAUCAAUCUCAUCAGAUUAGUGUGAGAAUACAUUCAUAUAAGUGCCAAGUACCUGCUAAGUGCUAGUCCAUGUGCUAAGUAAAUGUGAGCUGCAAUUGUUUGCCAUUGGCAUUAUCAGUAGAGUGGGAGUCUCAUUAUAGCAGAAACCUGGCUCUCCUGAACAUAUGUAAAUAUUUACAUAGCCCCUACUAAAUGCCAUUUAAGAGUGUAUCUAGUGUAAGGCAAUAGGAUGUGUUUAGCAGGAGGAGUGGAUUUGUUCAGGGGGUGCAACAGACUGGGAUGGGAGAAGAAGGCAUGUUUGAUAGUCAAAAUGCUGGCAUACUUCCUGCGCAAGGAAGUCUGUAUGGCUAAACAGUGCUGAACUAAACAAAUACUGCUGAAGGUCAGGUGUGAACAGUGAAUCAUAUUGGCGGGGCAUGGUCUGGGAUAUGGUGGUGAGCAGUAAAAACUACAAUAGCUACCAUGAAAGGUACCUACUAUAUGCCAGGCACUGUUCUAGUGCUUUUCUCCUAUUAGCCCUUGGAAGCAGUUCUAUUAUUAUCCCAUUUUGUAGAUUAGGAAACAGACUCAGAUUAAUUCAGUUACCCAAGGGGCACGUAACUGGUAAGUGGCAGAGCUUUGGUUCAGUCUCAGGCGUCGAGCUCUGGAGUGUGUGUGUGUGUGUGUGUGUGUGUGCUUUCAACCAUUGUGUUAGAUGCCUCUCAAGACAGAUAAGGUCCUUGCUAUUGUAGAAUUCACAGUCUAACUGAGUGAGCCAGUCAAACUAAUAAGUAUUAUAUCUAGUCUGCCAGGUAGUAAUAAAUGCAGUGAAGAGAAAAUUGGGUGAGGAAUUUUAGAGGAUGAUGGGAGUUGAUGUUUUAGCUAGUGUAUUAGUUUGUUCAGGCUGCCAUAAACAAAAUACCACAGAUUGGGAGGCUUAAACAACAGAAAUUUACUUUCUCACAGUUUUGGAGGCUGGAAAUCCAAGAGCAAGGUGUCAAUGUGUUUGGUUUCUUCUGAGGCCUCUGUCCUCGGCUUUGCAGAUGGCCCUUUCACUAUGUCCUUCUGUCUUCCCUCUAUGAGCGUUCAGCCCUGGGAGCUCUCUGUGCCCUGAUCACCUUUUCUUAUAAGGACAGUAGCCACACCUAAUCACCUCAUUUUAACUUAACCAUCUCUUUAAAGGCCCUGUCUUCAAAUACAGUCUCAUUUUGAGGUAUUAGGGGUUAGGACUUCAACAUAUAAAUUUGGGGAGGGGAACACAGUUCUGACCAUAACACUCUGCCCUCUGCACCCCCAAAAUUCAUGUCCUCCUCACAGCAAAAUACAUUCACCUGCAUUCAACAACCUAAGCCUUAACCCAUUCUAGCAUCAAUUCUAAGUCCCAAAUCUCAUCUAAAUAUCAUCUACAUCAAAGUGAGAGAGACUCAAGUAUAUGAUUCAUCUUGAGGCAAAAAUUCUUCUCCAGCUGUGAACCCGUGAAACCAGACAAGUUAUUUGCUUCCAAAAUACAAUGAUGGGGACAGGCUUAGGAUAGACAUUUCCAUUCCAAAAGGGAAAACUUGGAAGGAAGAAAAAAGGGUCAUGGGUCCAAAGCAAGUCCAAAACCUAGCUGGGCAAAUUAUGUUCAAUUUUAAGGCCUGAAAAUAAUUCUUUUUACAUGAUGAUCUGUCCUCCAGGCCCAUUGGGCUGGCAGAAUUUUUUUUUUUUUUUUUUCAGUAUUUAUUGAUCAUUCUUGGGUGUUUCUCGGAGUGGGGGAUUUGGCAGGGUCAUAGGACAAUAGUGGAGGGAAGGUCAGCAGAUAAACAUGUGAACAAGGGUCUCUGGUUUUCCUAGGCAGAGGACCCUGCUGCCUUCCGCAGUGUUUGUGUCCCUGGGUACUUGAGAUUAGGGAGUGGUGAUGACUCUUAAGGAGCAUGCUGCCUUCAAGCAUCUGUUUAACAAAGCACAUCUUGCACCGCCCUUAAUCCGUUUAACUCUGAGUGGACACAGCACAUGUUUCAGAGAGCACGGGGUUGGGGGUAGGGUCACCGAUCAACAGGAUCACAAGGCAGAAGAAUUUUUCUUAGUACAGAACAAAAUGGAGUCUCCCAUGUCUACUUCUUUCUACACAGACACAGUAACAAUCUGAUCUCUCUUUCUUUUCCCCACAUUUCCCCCUUUUCUAUUUGACAAAACCGCCAUCGUCAUCAUGGCCCGUUCUCAAUGAGCUGUUGGGUACACCUCCUAGACGGGGUGGCGGCCGGGCAGAGGGGCUCCUCACUUCCCACACGGGGCGGCCAGGCAGAGGCGCCCCUCACCUCCCUCCCGGAUGGGGCGACUGGCCGGGCGGGGGCUGCCCCCCACCUCCCUCCCGGACGGGGGUGGCUGGCCGGGCAGAGAGGCUCCUCACUUCCCGGACGGGGUGGCUGCCGGGCGGAGGGGCUCCUCACUUCCCAGACGGGGCGGCUGCGGGGCGGAGGGGCUCCUCACUUCUCAGAUGGGGCGGCCGGGCAGAGACGCUCCUCACCUCCCAGACGGGGUGGCGGUCGGGCAGAGACGCUCCUCACCUCCCAGACGGGGUCGGGGCCGGGCAGAGGCAAUCCUCACAUCCCUCACAUCCCAGACGGGGCGGCGGGGCAGAGGCGCUCCCCACAUCUCAGAUGAUGGGCGGCCGGGCAGAGAUGCUCCUCACUUCCUAGAUGGGAUGGCAGCUGGGAAGAGGCACUCCUCACUUCCCAGACUGGGCGGCCGGGCAGAGGGGCUCCUCACAUCCCAGAUGAUGGGCGGCCAGGCAGAGACACUCCUCACUUCCCAGACAGGGUGGCGGCCGGGCAGAGGCUGCAAUCUCGGCACUUUGGGAGGCCAAGGCAGGCGGCUGGGAGGUGGAGGUUGUAGCGAGCCGAGAUCACGUCACUGCACUCCAGCCUGGGCAACAUUGAGCACUGAGUGAGCGAGACUCCGUCUGCAAUCCCGGCACCUCGGGAGGCCGAGGCAGGCAGAUCACUCGCGGUCCAGAGCUGGAGACCAGCCCAGCCAACACGGCGAAACCCCGUCUCCACCAAAAAAUGCAAAAACCAGUCAGGCGUGGCUGCGCGUGCCUGCAAUCCCAGGCACUCUGCAGGCUGAGGCAGGAGAAUCAGGCAGGGAGGUUGCAGUGAGCCGAGAUGGCGGCAGUACAGUCCAGCCUCCGCUGGGCAUCAGAGGGAGACCUUGCAAAGAGGGAGACGGGAGAGGGAGACGGAGAGGGGGAGGGGGAGGGGAGGGGGAGGGGAGGGGGAGGGAGAGGACUGGCAGAAUUUCUUCAAGGCCCCAGGUGGCAGCCUUGCUUUUGAGGCCUUGGACAAUGACAGCCUCACCCUCUCACACUGAGACAGAGAGAGCCUCACCCUUUGAAAUGGAAGAGAGCCUUCCUCGCCCCUGGGCCUGAACACUUUCGUUGUGGGGUGAGAGUAGUAGCUUUAGGGACCAUUCUUCCUUUUUCUUGAAGGAUAAUACAUGCUCACACCCAGAGCCAGAUAGAUCUAUUGUCCCAUCCUGUAGCAUCUCAGAAGCCUGCUGCUGUUGUGUCCUGUCUCUGUCCCCUUUAGUCCAAGUCAGCAGUGUUUCUGCUACUGGUAGAACCCCGUCUCUAUUCCUGGCUUCUGUUGAGAUGGCCAAUUAGAUCUGUGAGUCCCACUGUCACUCUUUAGGGAGUGAUUGUCCAGUCACACUGUUGGUGCCCUCUCCAGAACACAUUCUCAUUUUUUUGCAAUAUGGAUAAGCUGAGAAUUUUCCAGAUCUUUAAGUUCUGGUUUGUUUAGCCUAACAAUUUUUUCUUUAAUUUCUCUCACUUCUCUUGCACUUUAAUAGAAGCAGUAAGGAGAAAGGAAAGUGGCAAGGAAAGCACAACAGGCUUUCAACACUUGGCUUAGAAAUCUCAGCAGAAUAUCCAAGGUUGUCACUUACAAGCUCUACCUUCCACAAAACACAAAAAUGCAAUUCAGCAAUGUUCUUGGCCAUUUUAUAACAAGGAUUGCCUUUUUUCAGUGUCUAAUAACAUGUUCCUCAUUUCUGUCUAAAAUCUCACUAGAAUCACCUUUCAUGUCCAUAUUUCUAGCAACAGUCUCUCUUAGCAUCUGAGACAACGUUCUGUGGAACACAGUUUGGGGAAGCUUGCCAAACUCAACAGAUUAUACUAUAUCAUCUCCCCCUGAAAGAGAAGAGUGAGACAUAAGUCCUCUGCAGUCUGUUCCACUCCUACUAGAUCUUGAAGUCAUAUGUUGAUUCUUUUCAUGGUAUUGUGUGCCUGUGUUUUAAGGAAAAUAAUUAGCAUUCUUAAAGCAAAGCAAAAAUUUUACUAAAGAAAAUAAUUAGCCUUUCAUGUCACUUUCUUAGAGUGAACCAAAUAAGUUUUGUAUGAGAGAAAGAUAGGGGCCCGUAGAUGCCCACUUUAGUUUUGCAGGGUGGGUUCCUACAGCCACGUUCCCCUGGGCUAAUAAGGCUAAUGGAAUCAUGGUGGCAGUUUUGCAUUGGCCUCCAGCUAAUGAAAAGUUUUGCCAUGAGAACUUAACUUAGUCCUUCUGAUGCUUUUACUGCCUGUUGACACAGAAGGUGGAAAAUGACCAACUAUGCUAUACAUAAAAACAAAGUCCAGAUAUUCUUAUAUUCUUUUAGAAUAUGUCUUAUGUGCUGAUUUUUAAAAUAUUAAGGGAAAAAUUGACUUGUGAUACUUGAAAGUUCAUAGAACAGGGCACUGCAUUAAAACAGGGCUUAUGCAAAUAAAACACAUUUUUCUGUUCUUGGCCAGCAGUUCUACCGUCAGGAUACUUAUUCCAUACAGCACUGUAUGAUACAGACCAAGAUUUAUAGUUGGUGAUUUCCUGAGUAACAACUCAGAUAGCAAAUGCCUCCACAAAACAACUUUCGUAUGUUCUGCAAGGCACAAAGUAGUACAAUAGAAAGGAUUGUUUGCUUCAGGAUUUUUGUGGGGUGGUUUCUUUUUCUUUUUCUUUUUUCUCCCACAAGACAGAAUUUUUCUUCUUGCCCUAAAAUUUGAAAGAUUUCUCCUUUCUCUCCCCUUCUGCCACAAGUAGUCCCACCCUAAAAAGGAAGAUGAGGUUCUCUAGCAACCCAUAAGAUGCUCAUAAGAAAUAGCUUAAACUUUUGCUUUGAAACAAGACAUUCACAUAUUGGGGUUGUGGGCCAAUAAACUAGUCAAUAGAAAGAAUGGGGAAGAAGCAGUGAAUGCAAGGACAGUGUUGGUGGGGAAGGGGGAAUAUUCUGGUUUUCGUUUCUGUGGAUUUUUAGGCCAAAUUUGAACACAGGCUCUUGAUGACACAUGAAGUAUCUCUAACUUGAUUUUAUGUAUGCACACUUUAUGUACUAUCUGUACAUAAGUCAUAGACAUAUAGAUUGGACUAGAAUUUAGAGUUCAGAAAUGAACACUCACUUGUACAGUCAGUUAAUUUUCAAUAAAGGUGCCAAGACAGUUCAACAAAGGUAGUCUUUUCAACUGGUGGUGCUGGGACAACUGGGUAGCCACAUGCAAAAGAAUGAAGUUAGACUCUCACCUCACAUCAUAUACAGAAAGUAGUUCAAAAUGGAUCAAAGACCUAAACUAUGAGAUAAAAGAGAAGAAAACAUAGGUAUAAAUAUAUAACAUAUAAAAUACCAAAAAUAUAAACAACAAAAGAAGAAAUAGAUAAAUGAGACUUCAUCAAGAUAAAAACAUUUUUGCUUCAGAUAACACCAUUAAGAAAGUGAAAAGACGGCUCACAGAAUGGAGGAAACACUUUCAAAUCAUAUACCAAAUAAGAAUCUUGUAUACUGAAUAUGUAAGGAACUCUUAUAACUCAAAAGUAAAAAGACAAAUAAUUCAACUAAAACAUGAGCAAUAGAUUUGAAAGACAUUUCUCCAAAAGUAUAUAAAUGGGCUAUAUGCAUAUAAAAAGAAGCUGAAUAUCAUUAGCCAUCAGGGAAAUGAAAAUCAAAACCAUAAUGAGAUGCCACUUUGCAUCCACUAGGAUGGCUGUAAUCAAAAAGACAGAAGAAUAUUGGUAAGGAUGUGAAGAAAUUGAAAUCCUCAUACACUGCUGGUGAGAAUGGGAAGUGGUACAGCUGUUUUGGAAAACAGUCUGGAAGUCCUAAAAAGAUGAAACAUAGAGUUACCAUAUGACCCAGCAAUUCUACUCUUGGGUAUAUACCCAAGGGAAAUGAGAACAUACAUCAGUGCAAAAACUAGUUCACAAGUGUUUACAGCAGUAUCAUUCACAAUAGUCAAAAAGUUAUGGGGGAAAAUAACAUGUCCAAAAACUGAUGAAUAAAUAAAUAAAUGUGAUAUAUCCAUACAAUGAAACAUUAUUCAAGAAAAAGAUAUGAAGUCCAGAUACAUCUUACAACAUAGAUGAACCUUGAAAACAUGCUAAGUGAAAGGUCACAAAAGGCCACAUAUUGUAUGAGUCUAUUUAUAUUUACAUGAAAUGUUCAGAAUAGGCAAAUCUAAAGACAGUAGAUUAGUGUGUUAGGGGCUUGGGGGUAAAUGGAGAAUGACUGUUUAUGGAUAUAAGGUUUCUUUUUCGGUGUAAGGAAGAUGUUCUAAAAUUGAUAAUGAUGAUGGUCUUUCAACCCUGUGAAUAUACUACAAACCAUUGCAUUAUACGUGUUAAGUGUUGAGUGUAUGAUGUGUGGAUUAUAUCUCAAUAAAGAUGUUAAACCACACACAGUCAUAUUACAUAAUUACACAGUCAUAUUGAAUUCCGUUAUAAUUUCAGAUUUAUGGACUAACACUGAAUACUCAGAGUAUUAAGCGACCUGUUCCAGUGCAUAUAGCUGGUGAUCACAGAGCCAGACUUCCUGAACAUCAGGCCAACUGUCUCUCCAUUGUGAUUGUUACAGGAAGUUUGACCCCAACAUACCAUACAAGUCACACUUAAAAUUUGUAUUGGUGUGGCCAGGUACCACUCACUUGUUCAUGUAACAGAUCAGCAAGCCCCUGAAACCGAGGCUGGCAAUAGCAGUUUAAUUCCUGCUCCUGUAAGGUUCAGUAGUGUAGGCUGGGGGUGAGGAGACACAACAGCUGCUGCUGCUUUUCUUUUUUUUAACCAACAAGAAUGACCUUGAAAACAUGGGGUUCUUUACCACACAAUUAUUCAGGGACCCUGUCUGAUGGAAGUUCUUCUACCUUCUCCAGCCAGCAGAUGGGGAGGAGAGAGAGGAGGUUUAUCCAUGGGAGGUUUUCCUGAGCCACACUUAGGGGUGGUGCACCUCUCACACUCAUUUCCCCACACCUUCUGUGGUUACAACCCAGUCACUUGGCACCUUACAGAUGCUGUGGGGCUACGAAUGCAGACUCUGGUAUUGAAGGAGCUACAUUGUCUGGGGUAUAUACCCUGGGGUUUGUUGUCGCCUGCCAGGAAAAUUUAGGACACAUACACAAGGAGUUUAGGAGCAGAAGGUUAAUAGGUAGAAGAGAAGAGAGAGAAACAGCUUCCUCUGUAAAGGAGGGGGUCUCCCAGCAGAAAGGACCUGCUGGUGGUGAAUGCCUCGAGUGUUAUAGUAGGGUUUCAAGAGGCAGUGUCUGAUUUACCUAGAGCUCAUAGAUUGGUUCAAUCAGGUAUGACAUUUACAUAGUGCGGGGAAGGCUGGUUUCCCCACCCUAAUCUUCUUAUGCAAAUGGGCUGUCCAGUUAGGGCCAUCUUGUCUGCUCCUUUACAGUACAGGUGGCUGGCAGAGAAGGGAAGAUGGAGCCGCCAUCUUGAACAUGUCUACUCCUUAGUUCCCGCUGGCAUUCACCUGUGCAAGCUCCCAGCUUGCUGGCUGCUCUUUGAUAGAAAAUGAUUUGGGGCUGCUUUUCAUUAAAAAGAAGAACCUUACCAAGGACUCCCAUACCCUUGCUAUCUGCCUGCGUGAUUUCUUCUUAACUCCUAUAUCCCUAUCUGGGCUUGAAGUUUUCUCCUUAUACUUAAAAAAUCAAUCCAAAGGCUAGUCAGCCCGCAUGAUGACUGGGCACAAGUUUAGAAGUUUCAUAUCAUGGCUCCUGCUUCAUUGUGAGGGAUUUUAAUACCUUUAGAGCAAUGUUAAGUACCCAGUCUGACUGGUUAUUCUGUCAGCAGAGUCUGUCACCUGUCCUAGAAGAAUAGUCUUGUUUGUUGCUCCUAGACUGGCUGAUGAUUGAUAGGAGUUUCCAAGUUGUAUCUUAUUGGAAGGACCUUUGAGAGCUCUAGGCCUGUGGGCCUUCCUGAGGAGGUGACUGCAUUUGAAUAGGCUCUAAGUUUCCUAUAUCUUGCCUCUGCCCUGCUACAGCACUACAAGGGGAAACCUGGACCAUUUACCCUGCCUGUUGCAAGGUGGAUGGAAGUUUGCUUAGUUGAAGAAUUGCCACCAACCACUGAAUUGGAAGAAGGGCUCCGGAAUGGAGUUUACCUUGCAAAGUUAGCCAAGUUCUUUGCCCCGAAAAUGGUAUCAGAGAAAAAGAUCUAUGAUGUGGAACAAACACGUUAUAAGAAGUCUGGCCUUCAUUUUCGACACACAGAUAAUACCGUCCAGUGGUUAAGAGCGAUGGAGUCUAUUGGUCUACCCAAGAUAUUUUAUCCAGAAACAACAGAUGUCUAUGAUCGGAAAAACAUACCAAGAAUGAUAUAUUGCAUUCACGCACUGAGUUUGUAUCUGUUCAAACUAGGAAUAGCACCCCAGAUCCAGGAUUUGUUGGGCAAAGUAGACUUCACAGAGGAGGAAAUCAGUAAUAUGAGAAAAGAACUUGAGAAAUAUGGAAUACAGAUGCCAUCUUUCAGCAAAAUAGGUGGUAUUCUGGCCAAUGAACUGUCCGUGGAUGAAGCUGCAUUACAUGCUGCAGUUAUAGCCAUUAAUGAAGCAGUUGAAAAAGGAAUAGCAGAGCAAACCGUUGUAACACUAAGAAACCCAAAUGCGGUUUUAACUUUAGUGGAUGACAACCUUGCACCAGAAUAUCAGAAAGAACUCUGGGAUGCCAAAAAGAAAAAAGAGGAAAAUGCAAGACUGAAGAAUAGCUGUAUUUCAGAAGAAGAAAGAGAUGCUUAUGAAGAACUGCUGACACAAGCAGAAAUCCAAGGCAAUAUUAAUAAAGUCAACAGGCAGGCUGCAGUGGACCAUAUCAAUGCUGUCAUUCCGGAAGGUGACCCCGAGAAUACGCUGCUUGCACUGAAGAAACCAGAGGCCCAGCUGCCUGCUGUUUAUCCCUUUGCUGCUGCCAUGUAUCAGAACGAACUUUUCAACCUCCAGAAACAGAACACCAUGAACUACUUGGCCCACGAGGAGCUUUUGAUUGCUGUGGAAAUGUUGUCUGCUGUUGCUUUACUAAACCAGGCCUUGGAAAGCAACGAUCUUGUGUCUGUGCAGAAUCAACUCAGAAGCCCCGCAAUAGGCUUAAACAAUCUGGACAAGGCAUAUGUGGAACGUUAUGCAAACACACUACUCUCUGUUAAACUAGAAGUUUUAUCCCAAGGGCAAGAUAACUUAAGCUGGAAUGAAAUUCAGAAUUGUAUUGAUAUGGUUAAUGCUCAAAUUCAAGAAGAAAAUGACCGAGUUGUAGCUGUAGGGUACAUCAAUGAAGCUAUUGAUGAAGGGAAUCCUUUGAGGACUUUAGAAACUUUGCUCCUACCUACUGCGAAUAUUAGUGAUGUGGACCCAGCCCAUGCCCAGCACUACCAGGAUGUUUUAUACCAUGCUAAAUCACAGAAACUCGGAGACUCUGAGAGUGUUUCCAAAGUGCUUUGGCUGGAUGAGAUACAGCAAGCCGUCGAUGAUGCCAACGUGGACAAGGACAGAGCAAAACAAUGGGUUACUCUGGUGGUUGAUGUUAAUCAGUGUUUGGAAGGAAAAAAAUCAAGUGAUAUUUUGUCUGUAUUGAAGUCUUCCACUUCUAAUGCAAAUGACAUAAUCCCGGAGUGUGCUGACAAAUACUAUGAUGCCCUUGUGAAGGCAAAAGAGCUCAAAUCUGAAAGAGUGUCUAGUGACGGUUCAUGGCUCAAACUCAACCUGCACAAAAAAUAUGACUACUAUUACAACACUGAUUCAAAAGAGAGUUCCUGGGUCACACCUGAAUCAUGCUUGUAUAAAGAAUCAUGGCUCACAGGAAAAGAAAUCGAGGACAUUAUUGAGGAAGUCACAGUAGGUUACAUUCGUGAGAAUAUAUGGUCUGCUUCAGAAGAGUUGCUUCUUCGCUUUCAAGCCACAAGCUCAGGACCCAUCCUUAGGGAAGAGUUUGAAGCUAGAAAAUCAUUUUUGCAUGAACAAGAAGAGAAUGUGGUCAAAAUACAGGCUUUUUGGAAAGGAUAUAAACAACGGAAGGAGUAUAUGCACAGGCGGCAAACGUUCAUUGAUAAUACUGAUUCUAUUGUGAAGAUUCAGUCCUGGUUCCGAAUGGCAACUGCAAGAAAGAGCUAUCUUUCAAGACUACAGUAUUUCAGAGAUCAUAAUAAUGAAAUUGUGAAAAUACAGUCACUGUUGAGAGCGAACAAAGCUAGAGAUGACUACAAAACAUUGGUUGGCUCUGAAAACCCACCAUUAACAGUAAUUCGCAAAUUUGUAUACCUGCUGGACCAAAGUGAUUUGGAUUUCCAGGAGGAACUAGAGGUUGCACGAUUAAGGGAAGAAGUAGUGACCAAGAUCAGGGCCAAUCAACAGCUGGAAAAAGACCUGAACCUGAUGGACAUCAAGAUUGGACUGCUGGUGAAGAACAGGAUCACACUAGAGGAUGUAAUUUCACAUAGUAAAAAGCUGAACAAGAAAAAAGGAGGAGAAAUGGAAAUACUGAAUAACACCGACAACCAAGGAAUAAAAAGUUUGAGUAAGGAGAGGAGAAAAACACUAGAAACAUAUCAGCAGCUGUUUUACCUUUUACAGACCAACCCUUUAUACUUGGCUAAGCUGAUUUUCCAGAUGCCACAGAACAAGUCCACUAAAUUUAUGGAUACUGUUAUUUUCACACUAUAUAAUUAUGCCUCUAAUCAGCGAGAAGAAUAUCUACUUCUCAAGCUUUUUAAAACUGCUCUGGAGGAAGAAAUAAAAUCAAAAGUGGACCAGGUACAGGACAUAGUUACUGGUAACCCUACAGUCAUCAAGAUGGUCGUCAGCUUCAAUAGAGGUGCCCGGGGACAGAACACCCUGCGCCAACUCCUGGCUCCAGUGGUAAAAGAGAUCAUCGACGACAAGUCGCUGAUUAUCAACACAAACCCUGUAGAGGUGUACAAGGCUUGGGUGAACCAACUAGAAACACAGACUGGAGAGGCCAGCAAGUUGCCUUAUGAUGUGACCACAGAACAAGCUCUAACAUACCCAGAAGUGAAAAAUAAACUGGAGGCUUCCAUUGAGAACCUGAGAAGGGUCACCGACAAAGUCCUGAAUUCUAUCAUUUCUUCCCUUGAUCUACUGCCUUAUGGAUUGAGGUAUAUAGCCAAAGUACUGAAGAAUUCGAUCCAUGAGAAAUUCCCCGAUGCAACAGAAGAUGAGCUAUUAAAGAUUGUUGGAAACCUCCUGUACUAUCGGUACAUGAAUCCAGCCAUUGUAGCUCCAGAUGGCUUUGAUAUCAUCGACAUGACAGCUGGAGGUCAGAUAAAUUCUGACCAAAGGAGAAACUUAGGAUCAGUGGCCAAGGUUCUUCAGCACGCAGCCUCCAACAAGCUGUUUGAAGGAGAAAAUGAGCAUCUCUCAUCUAUGAACAAUUAUUUAUCAGAGACGUAUCAGGAAUUCAGGAAAUAUUUCAAAGAAGCAUGUAAUGUCCCUGAGCCAGAAGAGAAGUUUAAUAUGGACAAAUACACAGACCUGGUGACAGUCAGCAAACCAGUCAUUUAUAUUUCAAUUGAAGAAAUCAUCAGCACACACUCACUCCUGUUGGAACACCAGGAUGCAAUUGCCCCUGAGAAAAAUGACUUACUGAGUGAAUUGCUGGGGUCGCUGGGAGAGGUGCCAACCGUGGAAUCUUUUCUUGGGGAAGGAGCAGUUGACCCCAAUGACCCUAACAAGGCAAAUACACUAAGUCAGCUUUCAAAGACCGAGAUUUCUCUUGUCUUGACAAGCAAAUAUGACAUAGAGGACGGUGAAGCUAUAGAUAGCCGAAGCCUCAUGAUAAAGACCAAGAAGCUGAUAAUUGAUGUGAUCCGGAACCAGCCAGGGAACACAUUGACAGAAAUCUUAGAGACACCAGCAACUGCGCAACAGGAGGUAGACCAUGCCACGGACAUGGUGAGCCGUGCAAUGAUAGAUUCCAGGACUCCAGAAGAAAUGAAGCAUAGCCAAUCUAUGAUUGAAGAUGCACAGCUGCCUCUUGAGCAGAAGAAGAGGAAAAUCCAGAGGAAUCUUCGGACGUUGGAACAGACUGGACACGUGUCAUCCGAAAAUAAAUACCAAGACAUUCUCAAUGAGAUUGCCAAGGAUAUUCGAAAUCAAAGAAUCUAUCGUAAGCUUCGAAAAGCUGAAUUGGCAAAACUUCAGCAGACCCUGAAUGCACUUAACAAGAAGGCAGCAUUUUAUGAAGAGCAAAUCAAUUAUUAUGACACCUACAUAAAGACUUGUUUAGACAACUUAAAAAGAAAAAAUACUCGGAGAUCAAUUAAACUAGAUGGAAAAGGAGAACCCAAAGGGGCGAAGAGAGCGAAGCCAGUGAAGUACACUGCAGCAAAGCUGCAUGAGAAAGGUGUCCUGCUAGAUAUAGAUGAUCUUCAAACAAACCAGUUUAAGAAUGUUACAUUUGAUAUCAUAGCUACUGAAGAUGUAGGCAUUUUCGAUGUAAGAUCAAAAUUCCUUGGUGUUGAGAUGGAAAAGGUGCAACUCAAUAUUCAGGAUUUACUUCAGAUGCAAUAUGAAGGAGUAGCUGUAAUGAAAAUGUUUGAUAAGGUUAAAGUGAAUGUAAACCUUCUCAUAUACCUGCUGAACAAGAAGUUCUAUGGAAAGUGAAGUGCCUACAGAAAUUUCUUGGAUUCUGUAUCAUCUGGAUUAGGAAAUGAAUUUGUUUAAUAUUUUUGUUUUUAAACAUGAUUGAAAUCACUGCUUAUAAAUGUGUGAUUUUUUUAAAACGACCAAAACUGUUCUGAAGAAUGUACCCAGGUGCCUUUUUGCUAAUUUGAUACUAUAAUAGAAUGAGACAUAAAAUGAAUUAAUGGAAACAUAUCCACACUGUACUGUGAUAUAGGUACUCUGAUUUAAAACUUUGGACAUCCUGUGAUCUGUUUUAAAGUUGGGGGGUGGGAAAUUUAGCUGACUAGGGACAAACAUGUAAACCUAUUUUCCUAUGAAAAAAAUUUUAAAUGUCCCACUUGAAUAACGUAAUUCUUCAUAGUUUUUUUAAUCUAUGGAUAAAUGGAAACCUAAUUAUUUGUAAUGAAUUAUUUAGACAGUUCUAAGCCCUGUCUUCUGGGAGUUAUCAAUUUUAAAGAGAACUUUUGUGCAAUUCAAAUGAAGUUUUUAUAAGUAAUUGAAAAUGACAACACAAUAACACUUUCUGUAUAAAAGUAUAUAUUUUAUGUGAUUUAUUCCUACUAAAUGAAAGUGCACUACUGCCUCAUGUAAAGACUCUUGCACGCAGAGCCUUUAAGUGACUAAGGAACAACAUAGAUAGUGAGCAUAGUCCCCACCUCCACCCCUCACAAUUUAUUUGAAUACUUCAAUUGUGCCUCUCAAUUUUUUGUAAUGCUAAAAAAUCAGUAUCUAGAUGGUUUUUAAAUGUAUUCUCUGGAAAUUGUUUUAUGUAAAAUAAAUGUUACUUAAUUCCAUUAA